ACCGGCCGUUGGAGCCGCAUGGAUGGCAGCAGCAGGCCUGCCGGGCCCAGCGCGAGCUCCUCUCCACUGUGCACCAUGGUCCAGCGGUGGCUGCUGCUGUCCUGCUGCGGAGCCCUGCUCAGCGCUGGUCUGGCUAACACCUCCUACACCAGCCCAGGCCUCCAGAGGCUGAAGGACUCUCCACAGACAGCCCCGGACAAAGGCCAGUGCUCCACGUGGGGGGCUGGUCACUUCUCCACCUUCGACCACCACGUGUACGACUUCUCGGGGACGUGCAACUACAUCUUCGCGGCCACCUGCAAGGACGCCUUCCCCACCUUCAGUGUCCAGCUGCGGCGAGGCCCAGACGGGAGCAUCUCGCGGAUCAUCGUGGAGCUGGGGGCCUCCGUCGUCACUGUGAGCGAAGCCAUCAUCUCAGUCAAGGACAUCGGGGUCAUCAGCCUGCCCUAUACCAGCAAUGGACUCCAGAUCACACCCUUCGGCCAGAGCGUGCGGCUGGUGGCCAAGCAGCUGGAGCUGGAGCUGGAAGUCGUGUGGGGUCCUGACAGCCACCUCAUGGUUCUGGUGGAGCGGAAGUACAUGGGUCAGAUGUGCGGGCUCUGCGGGAACUUUGACGGGAAGGUGACCAACGAGUUUGUCAGUGAGGAGGGCAAGUUCCUGGAACCCCACAAGUUUGCUGCCCUCCAGAAGCUGGACGACCCCGGCGAGAUCUGCACCUUCCAGGACAUCCCCAGCACCCACGUCCGGCAGGCCCAGCACGCCCGGAUCUGCACCCAGCUGCUGACCCUGGUGGCCCCUGAGUGCAGCGUGUCCAAGGAGCCCUUCGUGCUAAGCUGCCAGGCGGACGUGGCCGCAGCCCCCCAGCCAGGCCCACAGAACAGCAGUUGUGCCACCCUGUCGGAGUACUCCCGCCAGUGCAGCAUGGUGGGCCAGCCGGUCCGCCGCUGGCGGAGCCCCGGCCUGUGCUCCGUGGGUCAGUGCCCGGCCAACCAGGUGUACCAGGAGUGCGGCUCGGCCUGCGUGAAGACCUGCUCCAACCCGCAGCACAGCUGCUCCAGCUCCUGCACCUUCGGGUGCUUCUGCCCGGAAGGUACGGUCCUGAAUGACCUCUCCAAUAACCACACCUGCGUGCCCGUCACCCAGUGCCCCUGUGUGCUCCACGGCGCCAUGUAUGCCCCCGGGGAGGUCACAAUAGCUGCCUGCCAAACCUGCCGGUGCACCCUGGGCCGCUGGGUGUGCACGGAGCGGCCGUGCCCCGGACACUGCUCCCUGGAAGGUGGCUCCUUUGUUACCACAUUUGACGCCAGGCCCUACCGCUUCCACGGCACCUGCACCUACAUCCUCCUCCAGAGCCCCCAGCUUCCCGAGGACGGUGCCCUCAUGGCUGUGUACGACAAGUCCGGCGUCUCACACUCCGAGACCUCCCUGGUGGCUGUGGUCUACCUCUCCAGGCAGGACAAAAUUGUGAUCUCUCAGGACGAGGUGGUCACCAACAACGGAGAAGCCAAGUGGCUGCCAUACAAGACUCGCAACAUCACGGUCUUCAGGCAGACGUCCACCCACCUCCAGAUGGCCACCAGCUUCGGGCUGGAGCUCGUGGUCCAGCUGCGCCCCAUCUUCCAGGCCUAUGUCACUGUUGGGCCCCAGUUCAGAGGUCAGACCAGAGGGCUCUGCGGCAACUUCAACGGGGACACAACGGAUGACUUCACCACUAGCAUGGGUAUCGCCGAGGGCACCGCCUCGCUGUUUGUGGACUCCUGGCGGGCGGGGAACUGUCCGGCCGCUCUGGAGCGUGAGACUGACCCCUGCUCCAUGAGCCAGCUCAACAAGGUGUGUGCAGAGACCCACUGCUCCAUGCUGCUGAGGACAGGCACGGUGUUCGAGAGGUGCCACGCCACAGUGAACCCUGCACCCUUCUACAAGAGGUGCGUGUACCAGGCCUGCAACUACGAGGAGACCUUUCCCCACAUCUGUGCCGCCCUGGGCGACUACGUACACGCCUGCUCCUUGCGGGGCGUCCUGCUCUGGGGCUGGAGAAGCAGUGUGGACAACUGCACCAUCCCCUGCACGGGUAACACCACCUUCAGCUACAACAGCCAAGCCUGUGAGCGCACCUGCCUGUCGCUGUCGGACCGUGCCACCGAGUGCCACCACAGCGCCGUGCCCGUGGACGGUUGCAACUGCCCCGAUGGCACCUACCUGAACCAAAAGGGCGAGUGUGUGCGCAAGGCCCAGUGCCCGUGCAUACUGGAGGGUUACAAGUUCAUCCUGGCCGAGCAGUCCACUGUCAUCAACGGCAUCACCUGCCACUGCAUCAACGGGCGGCUGAGUUGCCCGCAGCGGCCACAGAUGUUCCUGGCCUCCUGCCAGGCCCCUAAGACCUUCAAGUCCUGCAGCCAGUCCUCCGAGAACAAGUUUGGGGCAGCCUGUGCCCCCACAUGCCAGAUGCUGGCCACCGGUGUUGCCUGCGUGCCCACCAAGUGUGAGCCUGGCUGUGUCUGCGCCGAGGGCCUCUACGAGAAUGCCGACGGGCAGUGUGUGCCCCCCGAGGAGUGCCCAUGUGAGUUCUCGGGGGUCUCCUACCCUGGAGGAGCUGAGCUCCACACUGACUGCAGGACCUGCUCCUGCUCAAGGGGGAGGUGGGCCUGUCAGCAGGGCACCCACUGCCCAUCCACCUGCACCCUCUACGGGGAGGGCCACGUCAUCACCUUCGACGGCCAGCGCUUCGUAUUCGACGGCAACUGCGAGUACAUCCUGGCCACGGACGUCUGUGGUGUCAACGACUCACAGCCCACCUUCAAGAUCCUGACAGAGAACGUCAUCUGUGGGAACUCCGGGGUCACAUGCUCACGGGCCAUCAAGAUCUUCCUGGGGGGCCUGUCCGUGGUGCUGGCGGACAGAAACUACACGGUCACCGGGGAGGAGCCCCACGUGCAGCUCGGGGUGACGCCGGGUGCGCUGAGCCUUGUCGUGGACAUCAGCAUCCCCGGGAGGUACAACCUGACGCUCAUCUGGAACAGGCACAUGACCAUCCUCAUCAGGAUCGCCCGUGCCUCCCAGGAUCCCCUCUGCGGCUUGUGUGGCAACUUCAACGGGAACAUGAAGGACGACUUCGAGACGCGCAGCAGGUACGUGGCAUCCAGCGAGCUGGAGUUGGUGAACUCGUGGAAGGAGAGCCCGCUGUGCGGGGACGUGAGCUUCGUGACAGACCCCUGCAGUCUCAAUGCCUUCCGGCGCUCCUGGGCCGAGCGCAAGUGCAGCGUCAUCAACAGCCAGACCUUUGCCACCUGCCACAGCAAGGUAUACCACCUGCCCUACUACGAGGCCUGCGUGCGCGACGCAUGUGGGUGUGACAGUGGCGGGGACUGUGAGUGUCUGUGCGAUGCCGUGGCUGCCUACGCCCAAGCCUGUCUGGACAAGGGUGUGUGCGUGGACUGGAGGACCCCGGCCUUCUGCCCCAUCUACUGCGGCUUCUACAACACGCACACGCAGGACGGCCAUGGCGAGUACCAGUACACACAGGAGGCCAACUGCACGUGGCACUACCAGCCCUGCCUCUGCCCCAGCCAGCCACAGAGCGUCCCAGGCAGCAACAUCGAAGGCUGCUACAACUGCUCCCAGGAUGAGUACUUCGACCACGAGGAGGGGGUGUGCGUGCCCUGCAUGCCGCCCACCACGCCGCAGCCACCCACCACGCCGCAGCUGCCCACCACAGGCUCACGGCCCACGCAAGUCUGGCCCAUGACGGGAACCUCCACCACCAUCGGGCUUCUCAGCUCCACCGGACCCUCACCCAGCUCUAAUCACACCCCUGCCAGCCCCACCCAGACACCCCUCCUUCCAGCCACGCUCACAUCCUCCAAGCCCACAGCCUCCUCGGGAGAACCACCUAGACCAACCACGGCCGUCACCCCACAAGCCACAUCAGGGCUGCCUCCCACAGCCACACUGAGAUCGACAGCCACAAAACCCACAGUGACCCAGGCCACAACCAGGGCCACGGCGUCGACCGCCAGCCCAGCCACGACGUCCACAGCUCAGUCCACAACACGGACCACAAUGACACUACCAACCCCAGCCACAUCAGGGACAAGCCCCACGCUGCCAAAAUCGACCAAUCAGGAACUGCCAGGAACAACGGCCACCCAGACGACAGGCCCACGUCCAACCCCAGCAAGCACCACAGGCCCAACCACCCCACAGCCAGGACAACCCACGAGGCCCACAGCCACAGAGACCACUCAAACAAGAACGACUACUGAAUACACAACGCCCCAAACCCCACACACCACACACUCCCCGCCUACGGCGGGGAGUCCCGUCCCUUCCACAGGUCCUGUCACUGCAACAUCUUUCCAUGCCACCACUACCUAUCCAACCCCAUCACACCCUGAGACCACACUUCCCACUCACGUUCCACCUUUCUCCACCUCCUUGGUGACUCCAAGUACUCACACAGUCAUCACCCCUACCCACGCACAGAUGGCCACAUCUGCCUCCAACCACUCAGCGCCAACAGGUACCAUUCCUCCACCAACAACGCUCAAGGCCACAGGGUCCACCCACACAGCCCCACCAAUAACGCCGACCACCAGUGGGACCAGCCAAGCCCACAGCUCAUUCAGCACAAACAAAACACCUACCUCGCUACAUUCACACACUUCCUCCACACACCAUCCUGAAGUCACCCCAACUUCUACUACCACGAUUACUCCCAACCCCACUAGUACACGCACCAGAACCCCUGUGGCCCACACCAACUCAGCCACCAGCAGCAGGCCACCACCACCCUUCACCACACACUCCCCACCUACAGGGAGCAGUCCCUUCUCUUCCACAGGUCCCAUGACGGCAACAUCCUUCAAGACCACCACUACCUAUCCAACCCCAUCACUCCCUCAGACCACUCUUCUCACUCACGUUCCACCUUUCUCAACCUCUUUGGUGACUCCAAUUACUCACACAGUCAUCACCCCUACCCACCCACAGAUGUCCACUUCUGCCUAUAUCCACUCAACGCCAACAGGCACGAUUGCUCCACCAACAACAGUUAAGGCCACAAGGUCCACCUACACAGCCCCACUAAUGACGGCAACCACCAGUAGGAUCAGCCAAGCCCACAGCUCAAUCAGCACAGCCAAAACCUCUACAUCCCUCCACUCACAUGCUUCCUCCACACACCAUCCUGAAGUCACCCCAACUUCUACCACCAACGUGACUCCCAAGUCCACCAGUAGAGGCACCAGCACCCCUGUGACCCACACCACCUCGGCCACCAGUAGCAGGCCACCCACACCCAUCACAACACACUCUUCACCUACCAGGAGCAGUCCCCUCUCUUCCACAGGUCGUAUGACUGCAACAUCUCUCAAGACCACCACUACCUAUCCAACCCCAUCACAAGCUCACAUCACACUUCCCAUUCAUGUUCCACCUUUCUCCACCUCAUCGGUGACUCCAAGUACUCACACAGUCAUCACCCCAACCCACCCACAGAUGUCCACUUCUGCCUCCAACCACUCAACGUCAACAGGCACCAUUCCUCCACUGACAACGCUCAUGGCCACAGGGUCCACACACACAGCCCCACUAAUAACAGUGACCACCAGUAGGACCAGCCAAGUCCACAGCUCCUUCAGCACAGCCAAAACCUCUACAUCCCUCCUCUCCCAUGCUUCCUCCACACACCAUCCAGAAAUCACCACAAAUUCUACCACCACCAUUACUCCCAACCCCACUAGUACAGGCACCGGAACCCCUGUGGCCCACACCACCUCAGCCACCAGCAGCAGGCCACCACCACCCUUCACCACACACUCCCCACCUACAGAGAGCAGUCCCCUCUCUCCCACAGGUCCUAUGACUCCAACAUCCUUCAAGACCACCACUACCUAUCCAACCACAUCACACCCUCAGACCACACUUCCCACUCACGUUCCACCUUUCUCCAGCUCGUCAGUGACUCCAAGUACUCACACAGUCAUCACCCCUACCCAUGCACAGAUGUCCACUUCUGCCUCGAUCCACUCAACGCCAACAGGUACCAUUCCUCCACUGACAACGCUCACGGCCACAGGGUCCACACACACAGCCUCACCAAUGACGGGGACAACCAUUCGGACCACCCAAGCCCACAGCUCAUUCAGCAUAGCCAAAACCUCUACAUCCAUCCUCUCACAUGCUUCCUCCACACACCAUCCGGAAACCACACCAACUUCUACCACCAACAUUACUCCCAAGUCCACUAGUGCAGGAACCAGCACCCCUGUGGCCCACACCACCUUGGCCACCAGCAGCAGGCCACCCACACCCUUCACCACACACUCCCCACCUACAGGGAGCAGUCCCAUCUCUUCCACAGGUCCUAUGACUGCAACAUCCAUCAAGACCACCACGACCUAUCCAACCCCAUCACACCCUCAGACCACACUUACCACUCAUGUUCCACCUUUCUCCACCUCAUCAGUCACUCCAAGUACUCACACAGUCAUCACCCCUACCCACGCACAAAUGUCCACUUCUGCUUCGAUCCACUCAACGCCAACAGGCACCGUUCCUCCACUGACAACGCGCAUGCCCACAGGGUCGACACACACAGGCCCACCAAUGACGGGGACCAUUAUUCAGACAAGCAAAGCUCACAACUCAUUCAGCACAGCCAAAACUUCUACAUCUCUCCACUCACAUGCUUCCUCCACACACCAUCCUGAAACCACACCAACUUCUACCACCAACAUUACUCCCAAGUCCACUAGUGCAGGAACCAGCACCCCUGUGGCCCACACCACCUUGGCCACCAGCAGCAGGCUACCCACAACCUUCACCACACACUUCCCACCUACAGGGAGCAGUCAUGUCUCUUCCACAGGUCCUAUGACUGCAACAUCCUCCCAGACCACCACUACCCAUCCAACCCCAUCACACCCUCAGACCACACUUCCCACUCACAUUCCACCUUUCUCCACCUCCUUGGUGACUCCAAGUACUCACACAGUCAUCACCCCUACCCACGCACAAGUGUCCACUUCUGCCUCCAUCCACUCAACACCAACAGGCACCAUUCCUCCACCUACAACGGUAAAGGCCACAGGCACAGGGUCCACGCACACAGCACCACGAAUGACAGUGACCACCAGCGGGACCAGCCAAGCGCACAGCUCUUUCAGCACAGCCAAAACCUCCACAUCCCUACACUCACAUGCUUCUUCAACACUCCAUCCUGAAGUCACCCCAACUUCUACCACCACCAUCACCCCCAACCCCACCAAUACAGGCAUCAGAACGCCUGUGGCAAACACCACCUCAGCCACCAGCAGCAGGCUAACCACACCCUUCACCACACACUCCCCACCUACAGGGAGCAGUCCCAUCUCUUCCACAGGUCCUAUGACUGCAACAUCCUUCCAGACCACCACUACAUAUCCAACCCCAUCACACCCUCAGACCACACUUCCCACUCACGUUCCACCUUUCUCCACCUCCUUGGUGACUCCAAGUACUCACACAGUCAUCACCCCUACCCACGCACAGAUGGCCACUUCCGCCUCCAUCCAUUCAACGCCAACAGGCACCAUUCCUCCACUGACAACGCUCAUGAACACAGGGUCCACACACACAGCCCCACCAGUGACGCCGACCACCAGUGGGACGAGCCAAGCCGCGAGCUCAUUCAGCACAGCCAAAACCUCUACAUCCUUACAUUCACACACUUCCUCCACACACCAUCCUGAAGUCACCCCAACUGCUACCACCAAAAUCACCACCAACCCCACCAGUAUAGGAAGCAGCACACCCAUGGCCCACACUACCUCAGCCACCAGCAGCAGGCUAACUACACCAUUCACCACACACUCCCCAUCUACAGGGAGCAGUCCUGUCUCUUCCACAGGUCCUAUGACUGCAACAUCCUUCCAGACCACCACUACCUAUCCAACACCAUCACUCUCUCAGACCACUCUUCCCACUUACGUUCCACCUUUCUCCACCUCCUUGGUGACUCCAAGUACUCACACAGUCAUCACCCCUCCCCGCACACAGAUGGCCACUUCUGCCUCCAUCCACUCAACGCCAACAGGCACCAUUCCUCCACCGACAACGCUCAAGGCCACAGGGUCCACCCACACAGCGCCAACAAGGACGCUGACCACCAGCGGGACCAGCCAAGCCCUGAGCUCAUUAAACACAGCCAAAACCUCUACAUCCCUACAUUCACACACUUCCUCCACACACCAUCCUGAAGCCACCUCAACUUCUACCACCAACAUCACCCCCAACCCCACCAGUACAGGAACUGGGACACCUGUGGCCCACACCACCUCAGCCACCAGCAGCAGGCUAACCACACCCUUCACCACACACUCCCCACCUACAGGGAGCACUCCCAUCUCUUCCACAGGUCCUGUCACUGCAACAUCCUUCCAUGCCACCACUACCUAUCCAACACCAUCACACCCUCAGACCACACAUCCCACUCACGUUACAUCUUUCUCCACCUCCUUGGUGACUCCAAGUACUCACACAGUCAUCACCCCUACCCACGCACAGAUGGCCACUUCUGCGUCCAUCCACUCAACGCCAACAGGCACCAUUUCUCCACCAACAACGCUCAAGGCCACAGGGUCCAUCCACACAGCCCCACCAAUGACGCCGACCACCAGUGGGACCAGCCAAUCCCCAAGCUCAUUUAGCAUGGCCAAAACUUCUACAUCCCUACCUUACCACACUUCCUCCACACACCAUCCUGAAGUCACCCCAACUUCUACCACCAACAUCACCCCCAAACACACCAGUACAGGCACAAGAACCCCUGUGGCCCACACCACCUCGGCCACCAGCAGCAAGCUACCCACACCCUUCACCACACACUCCCCACCUACAGGAAGCAGUCCCAUCUCUUCCACAGGUCCUGUCACUGCAACAUCCUUCCAGACCACCACUACCUAUCCAACCCCAUCACACUCUCACACCACACUUCCCACUCACGUUCCACCUUCCUCCACCUCCUUGGUGACUCCAAAUACUCACACAGUCAUCACCCAUACCCAUGCACAGAUGUCCACUUCUGCCUCCAUCCACUCAACGCCAACAGGCACCAUUCCUCCACCGACAACGCUCAAGGCCACAGGGUCCACCCACACAGCCCCACCAAUGACGCCGACCACCAGUGGGACCAGGCAAGCCCCAAGCUCAUUCAGCACAGCCAAAACUUCUACAUCCCUACAUUCACACACUUCCUCCACACACCAUCCUGCAGUCACCCCAACUUCUACCACCAACAUCACCCCCAACCACACCAGUACAGGCACCAGGACCCCUGUGGCCCACACCACUUCGGCCACCAGCAGCAGGCUACCCACACCCUUCACCACACACUCCCCACCGACAGGGAGCAGUCCCAUCUCUUCCACAGCUCCUGUCACUGCAACAUCCUUCCAGACCACCACUACCUAUCCAACCACAUCACAGUCUCAGACCACACUUCCCACUCACAUUCCACCUUUCUCCACCUCCUUGGUGACUCCAAGUACACACACAGUCAUCACCCCAACCCAUCAACAGAUGGCCACUUCUGCCUCCAUCCACUCAACGCCAACAGGCACCAUUCCUCCACUGACAACGCUCAAGGCCACAGGGUCCACCCACACAGCCCCACCAAUGACGCCGACCACCAGUGGGACCAGCCAAGCCCUGAGCUCAUUCAGCACAGCCAAAACCUCUACAUCCCUACAUUCACACACUUCCUCCACACACCAUCCUGAAGUCACCCCAACUUCUACCACCAUCACCCCCAAACCCACCAGUACAGAAACCGGCACCCCUGUGGCCGACACCACGUCAGCCACCAGCAGCAGGCUACCCACACCCUUCACCACACACUCCUUACCUACAGGGAGCAGUCCCUUCUCUUCCACAGGUCCUAUGACUGCAACAUCCUUCCAGACCACUACUACCUAUCCAACCCCAUCACACCCUCACACCACACUUCCCACUCACAUUCCACCUUUCUCCACCUCCUUGGUGACUCCAAGUACUCACACAGUCAUCACCACUACCCACGCACAGAUGUCCACUUCUGCCUCCAUCCACUCAACGCCAACAGGCACCAUUCCUCCACCAACAACGCUCAAGGCCACAGGGUCUACCCACACAGCCCCACCAAUGACGCCGACCACCAGUGGGACCAGCCAAGCCCCGAGCUCAUUCAGCACAGCCAAAACCUCUACAUCCUUACAUUCACACACUUCCUCUGCACACCAUCCUGAAGUCACCCCAACUUCUACCACCAUCACCCCCAAUCCCACCAGUACAGAAACCGUCACCCCUGUGGCCCACACCACCUCAGCCACCAGCAGCAGGCUAACCACACCCUUCACCACACACUCCCCACCUACAGGGAGCAGUCCCAUCUCUUCCACAGGUCCUGUCACUGCAACAUCCUUCCAUGCCACCACUACCUAUCCAACACCAUCACACCCUCAGACCACACUUCCCACUCACGUUCCAUCUUUCUCCACCUCCUUGGUGACUCCAAGUACUCACACAGUCAUCACCCCUACCCACGCACAGAUGACCACUUCUGCCUCCAUCCACUCAAUGCCAACAGGCACCAUUCCUCCACCGACAACGCUGAAGGCCACAGGGUCCACCCACACAGCCCCACCAAUGAUGCCAACCACCAGUGGGACCAGCCAAGCCUCAAGCUCAUUCAACACAGCCAAAACCUCUACAUCCCUACAUUCACACACUUCCUCCACACACCAUCCUGAAGUCACCCCAACUUCUAUCACCAACAUCACCCUCAACCCCACCAGUAUAGGAACCUGGACACCCGUGGCCCACACCACCUCAGCCACCAGCAGCAGGCUAACCACACCCUUCACCACACACUCCCCACCUACAGGGACCACUCCCAUCUCUUCCACAGGUCCUGUCACUGCAACAUCCUUCCAUGCCACCACUACCUAUCCAACACCAUCACACCCUCAGACCACACUUCCCACUCACGUUCCAUCUUUCUCCACCUCCUUGGUGACUCCAAGUACUCACAUAGUCAUCACCCCUACCCACGCACAGAUGGCCACUUCUGCCUCCAUCCACUCAAUGCAAACAGGCACCAUUCCUCCACCGACCACGAUCAAGGCCACAGGGUCCACCCACACAGCCCCACCAAUGACACCGACCACCAGUGGGACCAGCCAAUCCCUAAGCUCAUUUAGCACGGCCAAAACUUCUACAUCCCUACCUUACCACACUUCCUCCACACACCAUCCUGAAGUCACCCCAACUUCUACCACCAACAUCACCCCCAAACACACCAGUACAGGCACCAGAACCCCUGUGGCCCACACCACCUCGGCCACCAGCAGCAGACUACCCACACCCUUCACCACACAUUCCCCACCUACAGGGAGCAGUCCCAUCUCUUCCACAGGUCCUAUGACUGCACCAUCCUUUCAGACCACCACUACCUAUCCAACCCCAUCACACCCUCAGACCACACUUCCCACUCACAUUCCACCUUUCUCCACCUCCUUGGUGACUCCAAGUACUCACAAGGUCAUCACCCCUACCCAUGCACAGAUGUCCACUUCUGCCUCCAUCCACUCAACGCCAACAGGCACCAUUCCUCCACUAACAACGCUCAAGGUCACAGGGUCCACCCACACAGCCCCACCAAUCACAGUGACCACCAGUGGGACCAGCCCAUCCGCAAGCUCAUUUAGCACAGGCAAAACCUCUACAUCCUUACAUUCACACACUUCCUCCACACACUAUCCUGAAGUCACCCCAACUUCUACCACCACCAUCACCCCCAACCACACCAGUACAGGCACCAGAACCCCUGUGGCCCACACCACCUCGGCCACCAGCAGCAGGCUACCCAUACCCUUCACCACACAUUCCCCACCUACAGGGAGCAGUCCCAUCUCUUCCACAGGUCCUAUGACUGCAACAUCCUUUCAGACCACCACUACCUAUCCAACCCCAUCACACCCUCAGACCACACUUCCCACUCACCUUCCACCUUUCUCCACCUCCUUGGUGACUCCAAGUACUCACACAGUCAUCAUCACUACCCACACACAGAUGGCCACUUCUGCCUCCAUCCACUCAACGCCAACAGGCACCGUUCCUCCACCAACAACGCUCAAGGCCACAGGGUCCACCCACACAGCGCCAACAAUGACGCCGACCACCAGCGGGACGAGCCAAGCCCUGAGCUCAUUCAACACAGCCAAAACCUCUACAUCCCUACAUUCACAAACUUCCUCCACACACCUUCCUGAAGUCACCCCAACUUCUACCGCCAUCACCCCCAAUCCCACCAGUACAGGAACCGGCACCCCUGUGGCCCACACCACCUCAGCCACCAGCAGCAGGCUAACCACACCCUUCACCACACACUCCUCACCUACAGGGAGCAGUCCCUUCUCUUCCACAGGUCCUAUGACUGCAACAUCCUUCCAGACCACCACUACCUAUCCAACCCCAUCACACCCUCAGACCACACUUCCCACUCACGUUCCACCUUUCUCCACCUCUUUGGUGACUCCAAGUACUCACACAGUCAUCACCCCUACCCAUGCACAGAUGGCCACUUCUGCCUCCAUCCACUCAAUGCCAACAGGCACGAUUCCUCCACCGACAACGCUCAAGGCCACAGGGUCCACCCACACAGCGCCAACAAUGACGCCGACCACCAGCGGGACCAGCCAAGCCCUGAGCUCAUUAAACACAGCCAAAACCUCUACAUCCCUACAUUCACACACUUCCUCCACACACCAUGCUGAAGCCACCUCAACUUCUACCACCAACAUCACCCCCAACCCCACCAGUACAGGAACCCCACCAAUGACAGUGACCACCAGUGGGACCAGCCAAUCCCGAAGCUCAUUUAGCACGGCCAAAACCUCUACAUCCCUACAUUCACACACUUCCUCCACACACCAUCCUGAAGUCACCUCAACUUCUACCACCAGCAUCACCCCCAACCACACCAGUACAGGCACCAGAACCCCUGUGGCCCACACCACGUCGGCCACCAGCAGCAGGCUACCCACACCCUUCACCACACACUCCCCACCUACAGGGACCACUCCCAUCUCUUCCACAGGUCCUGUCACUGCAACAUCCUUCCAGACCACCACUACCGAUCCAACCCCAUCACACCCUCACACCACACUUCCCACUCACGUUCCAUCUUUCUCCACCUCCUUGGUGACUCCAAGUACUCACAUAGUCAUCACCCCUACCCACGCACAGAUGGCCACUUCUGCCUCCAUCCACUCAAUGCCAACAGGCACUAUUCCUCCACCGACCACGAUCAAGGCCACAGGGUCCACCCACACAGCCCCACCAAUGACGGCAACCACCAGUGGGACCAGCCAAUCCCCAAGCUCAUUUAGCACGGCCAAAACUUCUACAUCCCUACAUUCACACAUUUCCUCAACACAUCAUCCUGAAGUCACCCCAACUUCUACCACCACCAUCACCCCCAACCACACCAGUACAGGCACCAGAACCCCUGUGGCCCACACCACCUCGGCCACCAGCAGCAGGCUACCCAUACCCUUCACCACACAUUCCCCACCUACAGGGAGCAGUCCCAUCUCUUCCACAGGUCCUAUGACUGCAACAUCCUUUCAGACCACCACUACCUAUCCAACCCCAUCACACCCUCAGACCACACUUCCCACUCACCUUCCACCUUUCUCCACCUCCUUGGUGACUCCAAGUACUCACACAGUCAUCAUCACUACCCACACACAGAUGGCCACUUCUGCCUCCAUCCACUCAACGCCAACAGGCACCGUUCCUCCACCAACAACGCUCAAGGCCACAGGGUCCACCCACACAGCGCCAACAAUGACGCCGACCACCAGCGGGACGAGCCAAGCCCUGAGCUCAUUCAACACAGCCAAAACCUCUACAUCCCUACAUUCACAAACUUCCUCCACACACCUUCCUGAAGUCACCCCAACUUCUACCACCAUCACCCCCAAUCCCACCAGUCCAGGAACCGGCACCCCUGUGGCCCACACCACCUCAGCCACCAGCAGCAGGCUAACCACACCCUUCACCACACACUCCUCACCUACAGGGAGCAGUCCCUUCUCUUCCACAGGUCCUAUGACUGCAACAUCCUUCCAGACCACCACUACCUAUCCAACCCCAUCACACCCUCAGACCACACUUCCCACUCACGUUCCACCUUUCUCCACCUCUUUGGUGACUCCAAGUACUCACACAGUCAUCACCCCUACCCAUGCACAGAUGGCCACUUCUGCCUCCAUCCACUCAAUGCCAACAGGCACGAUUCCUCCACCGACAACGCUCAAGGCCACAGGGUCCACCCACACAGCGCCAACAAUGACGCUGACCACCAGCGGGACCAGCCAAGCCCUGAGCUCAUUAAACACAGCCAAAACCUCUACAUCCCUACAUUCACACACUUCCUCCACACACCAUGCUGAAGCCACCUCAACUUCUACCACCAACAUCACCCCCAACCCCACCAGUACAGGAACCCCACCAAUGACAGUGACCACCAGUGGGACCAGCCAAUCCCGAAGCUCAUUUAGCACGGCCAAAACCUCUACAUCCCUACAUUCACACACUUCCUCCACACACCAUCCUGAAGUCACCUCAACUUCUACCACCAGCAUCACCCCCAACCACACCAGUACAGGCACCAGAACCCCUGUGGCCCACACCACGUCGGCCACCAGCAGCAGGCUACCCACACCCUUCACCACACACUCCCCACCUACAGGGACCACUCCCAUCUCUUCCACAGGUCCUGUCACUGCAACAUCCUUCCAGACCACCACUACCUAUCCAACCCCAUCACACCCUCACACCACACUUCCCACUCACGUUCCAUCUUUCUCCACCUCCUUGGUGACUCCAAGUACUCACACGGUCAUCAUCCCUACCCACACACAGAUGGCCACUUCUGCCUCCAUCCACUCAAUGCCAACAGGCACCAUUCCUCCACCGACCACGAUCAAGGCCACAGGGUCCACCCACACAGCCCCACCAAUGACACCGACCACCAGUGGGACCAGCCAAUCCCCAAGCUCAUUUAGCACGGCCAAAACUUCUACAUCCCUACCUUACCACACUUCCUCAACACACCAUCCUGAAGUCACCCCAACUUCUACCACCAACAUCACCCCCAAACACACCAGUACAGGCACCAGAACCCCUGUGGCCCACACCACCUCGGCCAGCAGCAGCAGGCUACCCACACCCUUCACCACACACUCCCCACCUACAGGGAGCAGUCCCUUCUCUUCCACAGGUCCUAUGACUGCAACAUCCUUCCAGACCACCACUACCUAUCCAACCCCAUCACACCCUCAGACCACACUUCCCACUCACGUUCCACCUUUCUCCACCUCCUUGGUGACUCCAAGUACUCACACAGUCAUCAUCACUACCCACACACAGAUGGCCACUUCUGCCUCCAUCCACUCAACGCCAACAGGCACCGUUCCUCCACCAACAACGCUCAAGGCCACAGGGUCCACCCACACAGCCCCACCAAUGACAGUGACCACCAGUGGGACCAGCCAAACCCACAGCUCAUUCAGCACAGCUACAGCCUCUUCUUCCUUCAUAUCCUCCUCGUCUUGGCUGCCUCAGAACUCUAGCUCAAGGCCACCGUCAUCACCUAUCACCACACAACUCCCCCACUUGAGUUCUGCAACCACUCCUGUUUCCACAACUAAUCAGCUGUCCUCCUCAUUUUCUCCCAGUCCUUCUGCCCCCUCUACUGUUUCUUCUUAUGUGCCCUCCUCCCACUCCUCUCCCCAGACUUCAUCGCCUUCUGUUGGCACAUCUUCCUCUUUCGUGUCCGCCCCCGUGCACUCCACAACCCUGAGCUCGGGGUCACACUCCUCAUUGUCCACUCAUCCCACGACUGCAUCAGUGUCUGCAUCUCCUCUUUUUCCUUCUUCUCCAGCUGCCUCUACUACCAUUAGGGCCACUCUCCCCCACACUAUCUCCUCUCCUUUCACCCUCUCUGCUCUACUCCCCAUAUCCACUGUUACCGUGUCUCCCACCCCAUCCAGCCACCUAGCCUCCAGCACCAUUGCAUUUCCGUCCACGCCCAGGACCACGGCCAGCACCCACACCGCCCCUGCCUUCUCCUCUCAGUCCACCACCUCGCGGUCCACUUCUCUCACCACCCGAGUUCCCACAUCAGGCUUUGUGUCACUCACCUCGGGGGUGACGGGUAUCCCCACCUCUCCAGUCACCAACCUUACCACCAGGCACCCUGGUCCCACCUUGUCGCCUACCACACGGUUCCUGACCAGCUCCCUCACUGCCCAUGGAAGCACCCCUGCUUCUGCCCCGGUAUCUUCUCUCGGGACACCUACGCCCACCUCACCCGGGGUCUGCAGUGUGCGGGAGCAGCAGGAGGAGAUCACGUUCAAGGGGUGCAUGGCGAACGUGACGGUAACCCGCUGUGAGGGCGCCUGCAUUUCCGCUGCCAGCUUCAACAUCAUCACCCAGCAGGUGGAUGCCCGCUGCAGCUGCUGCCGCCCCCUCCACUCCUAUGAGCAGCAGCUGGAGCUGCCCUGCCCCGAUCCCAGCACGCCUGGCCGGCGGCUCGUACUCACCCUGCAGGUGUUCAGCCACUGCGUGUGCAGCUCUGUGGCCUGUGGAGACUAGCAGGGUCGCUGCCUGCUCUCCUGGGGCUGAAGGACUGCAGAUGACAGACAGGAAAACACCCACCAGCCCCCUUCCCGCUUGUGCCAGCAGCUGCUUUCCUGGUCACCAGGCCUGGCCCCCAAGUGCCCUGGGCCGUGGCUCCCUGGGGCACCGGUUGGAGAGGGGCUGCCAAGCAGGGGCUCAGACUACCACACUCCUGCAGACCCUGAGCCAGCAGAGAGGGACUGAGGCGGACAGUGGUCACGGACCUCCCAGGCACACAGGGCACUCCCGACCACCCCUGCCCACCGUCCAACACCUCCCAGCCCCUGAACUUGGCCCCAGCCCUGCUGGGCCCAGAACCCUGCAGAUGAAGCCACAGAGCAGGCGCUCGACCAGACCCAUCAGGGGCGAGGAGGGCACGGAAACCUGUGCCGAGAUGGGGGCAAGAGGCCCAGGCAGCCACCAGCACAGAGAAGAGGAGAUCCCCAGAGUCAGGGAGGGCAGAGGGUGGCAGCGAGGGCAGGGCAGCCGCCCCCGCUCCCAGCCAGGCAGAAGGCCCCCACCAGCACCACACCCAUCCCCAGCAGCCUGUCCUUGGGAGAGGGCGUCACCCGGUCAGAGACUCCAAAUAAACCGGUUCUUGUCAAGGCACA